AGACGGGUGUCAUGCGUUGGCCUUUUCAUCUAAGCCUCCACCCGCGCUGCAGGGCAUAGGACCCUGCAGCCCCUGGUGUCAAGCUGGGCUUUGCUGCAGCUCAGUCAUCUGUUGAAAAACAAUGUAUUUGUGUGCAUGUGUGCGUGUUGGAGGUGAUCCUUUGCUCUAAAUUCAGUUAGUAGGUUGCACUGAGGAGCAGGUAAACUUGGAGCCCAUUUAUCUUUGUUAUUUAGAAUCUUCUCUGUUGGACAAGGUGCUAUUCAUGCCCUCCCAGUAUGUCUCUUUGAUAGUAGUUUAAAAGGUGAUAUAAAAGCAGGUUAACUUUCACUUAACGAGGUUUUGUGGUCGGUCCUUCAUGAUCUGGAACAGGUUAUGACGGCAGGUAGAAGUCUACUUACAAAAAAAGUUUACUCCAUUUUAAAAGAAGAACUUAGAAUUUAGUUUUGUAUUUCUGGCAUAAUUGCCUUGUAGAAAAUACUUGCCCUGUGUGCUGCAUGCUUCAUUGGCCUUUGAGUUUUUAGUUGCAAAAUGAUACUACAAAAUAAACACUUUAAAAGAAAUACUUUUUGUUGAUAAAUGGCCCUUUUAAGUUCUAUGGUUAAGAUAAAAAAAAUCGAAGAGUGGAUUCAGUUCUCCGAGCGUUAGACGUUGAUGUGGUUUGAAAACAGUAGACUGAGAUUCCGCUUGUAUUUUUUGAAAUGCUAUACACAACAGUAAAUUAGCACAAGGGAAAAAACCUGAAGAUUUUUGUAUAAAAUAUUUGAAAGAGAAAGAAAUCGUGAAUUAUUCAAGUGUACAUAUCAUUGUUUCGUGAACCAUUGCUCAGAAUAAUGAUCUUAGCCGAAACUUGGAGAGGUGGGAGAAGGAGGAUCCUUAGUUUUUCAGAAGAAUGAAUAUGUGGUGAGUGGUCUUUAUAAAAGAUUUACUAUACUAUAAAGUUUUCUAGCUCUUUAUUACACAUGAAUUUCAAUUAUUGGUUUAGAUUGUGUUGUAGGUUUUAAAAGCACAUGGCUCUUCACUCAAAUGCCAUAUUCUGUCUUUGAAUUGUUUUAGUAACUAAUUGAAAUGUAGCUUGAGUAGUGUUACACUCACUCAUUCCACUAAAUCCCAGAUGGGUCUUUUAUUUAAUAGAAAAAAAAUACUGACAUUUCACAAAUUAGAUUUUGAAUUUGUAACUUGUAUUACUCACUACCCUAAGCAUAUCUUAUCACUACCCUAAGCAAGCCAUUUUCAAUAAAAAAAUAAUUUUGGAAAGUAAUAAAGAUGAAUUUCAAAAGGAGAGUUCGUUCAACCACAACGAAGAAUAAAAGUUUAUUUCAAGCGCUAAUGUCACUGUUAGAGUGUUCCACUGACUUUUGCCAUAAAUGUAUCAUUUCUCUUGAAAAGUCAAUAAUCAAAUGCUAGGAGGAAGCAAGGACUGAAGAAAUCCUUUUAGAAGAUGAAACUUCUCCAUCCUACACCCCAGCUUUAAUUUCCUAGAAGGGAGGCCAAGGCCUAGGUUUUCUUUCCUUGUGUAUUUUUUCUGUCUCCAUCACCCACACAACUGGAAUUGUCUAUGUAUAAUCAGUUUAAUUUUGAUCCUGGCCGGUCUUAUUUCAGAUGCUUAAUAUCCCCUCUCCCUUCCUAAUAAAUAGUGCCACAAUUUAGACAAGAUGUUUAAGCACAAGUCUAGUUCGCAUUUAAGCGUGAUUAAUCAAUAAUUGAUGGGUCUGCCUGAUCAUAAGAUUGGGUCAUGUACUUGUGAAAAUGCAUUCAAGUUUAGAGUACUUGAUUUGGGGAGAGGGAUACCACUGAGUAGGCAAAGCGGUAGAAGCUAAGAUAGACCAAAGCACAGACUUGGUAGAUUUUGCAUUUUUUGUUUUGGCCCAAAGUUGUUUAAACAGAGCCAGGAAGACUCAGUAGAUACUGUGCCCUGAAGUGUUUUUGCCAUGCUCCUGCAAACAUUGGUAGUUUACUCAUAAUGACCUCUGCAGUGUCUUUUUAAUAAAUCCGUCCGUCUCUCUGUUGUUAUUUUUAUAUAAUUAGUUAUGUUGCAAAAAGUCACCGUGAAAACUGGAUUAGCAAACACUGAACCACUGCUCCUACUAUGGUGUUAGAUUCCUGAAAGCUGCUGUUCACAACAUUUUUGUCAACUGAUCAAGAUACAACCUUGUUUUAUGUCUGUUGCAGUUUAAAUACACCUUAUUUAAUAUAUUUGGUUGAUUUAUUAACAUUGAAAUCAUGGCCAACAGCUCUGUAAAUCAUGCCUCAAUGAAGAUUAUCUCACACUUGUAUUUUCUCUGUAGUCUUUGCUCCUUGAACACUAGACAGCACUUUAGCACUACGCUUAGGGACUGUUUUCAACAGUGAAAUCACCAAUAGCAAGCACAAAAAUGAGAAAAACAUGGCACUAAAUAGACCAUGAAAAGGACACUUGUUUACACUAUGUAAGCUGAAACUAGAAUGUGCACGUCAGUAGACUCACAUUUUUCACCAUUGUGCACAUGUCUGCAAUGACAGUGGAAGUGCUAUGAGUAAUGAUUUUGGGGAUACAAAUAAAUGUUAGUGAGUAGAUGAAUUUGUAAAUAUAGUAUCCUCAACUAAUGAGGAGCAACCUUUGUUAUAGGUAGAUAUGUAUAUGCACAUAUUAUGUCUAUAAUUUGAAAAGCAGAUUCUCAGGGGUAGGUUGUAUGUUAUAACUAAACUGUUAAAGUUUUCUCUCUGAAACAUUAUAUACUUUGUAUCAUAAUGUCUUUGUAGUCAAGCACAUAAGUGUUUGAAAAUAGAACUUGCACCUUUUUAGUUCCUCCUCAAAGUUUAAAGGACUGAUAACAUAGUGAGGCAGUUCAUGUUUUUUUUCUCAAAAACAUGUUUAGGAGUCUGUACUAAGCAGAUCCCAGCUUUGGUCUGUAGAAAUGAGGGAGAGCGGUAUGUUGGUUUUAGCUUCAAACAGUGACAAAUUGUCAGGCUCAUAUAAUUAAUUCAAUGUAACCUUCCAAGUUUUUACUAAAACCUGGGGUUGGCUUGUUGACCACAUGCAUCACCAUAACAAGCCUUUGGUGCUAGUCUGAGGAAUUUAAUACUGAUUGAUAAUAAGUUGGUUUUUGAGUAGGGGACAUUGUUUUCCCUAAAUGUCCUUGGUACAAAAUGGACCUAAAAUGGGGUGUUGAGACUGGGAGAGCAGAGAUAACUUGUUGAGAUAAUGUAAUCACGAGGUUAUGGGGGCUGGGUAGGAAUGAUAGUGUGAAUAUGGUGAUGUGGGUAAGAUUUACUGAGAUGGGUGUUGGGGGUUAUUGGAUUGUUAGUAAUUGGAGGCCAGGAAUUUACUACAGGGUUCUUUAAAAAUAGCUCAGUAUUUCUCUUAGAGUUAAAUGCUUAGAUAAGCUAAGUAUUAGCCAGUUCUCGUUGUUAAUUUUUCAGGAAGGUUGUACUAUACAUCUGAUUUUGCACUAUAAAUUAGUAGGGAAAUGAUAGAUUUAAGCAUUAUAUCUCAUUUGCAGAAAGCAUCUGUGGCUGCCCAGUAACUUGUAAGUUCACAUUCCGAAGAGAAGAUAGAGAGGAUAGAAAAAAGGGAAGGAUCGAAUAAAAAUAUCAACAACUGUUACUACUACACAACUUCAUUAAAUGCCUUUGGUGUGCUAAGCACUGCUAGGUGCUACUUAACAUAGUAGAGGACAAUAGUGGAGGUAUUCUUCUGGCCUAUGAAACUUACAGAUUAGUGUGGAAGGUAAAAGCUAAACAAGCCAACAAAAAUCACCAAGUUACUAUAGUUAAAAUUUUUUAUAUGUGUCGUGAAGACAAUGCUCAGGGUUUUAUGAGAGAAUUCAGUUUAGACUGGGGGGUCAAGGAAGGCCUUUUUGAUCUUUUAGCAGAAACCUGAAGGAUGAAGAAAGUUAGGUAAAAACAGAGGUGUGAGGUUGGGGUGAUUUGAAGUAUGUCAUGAAGACUGAAGUCUCUGUGUGAGGGAAGGAAGUUUCAGAAACUGAAAUAUGCUCAGAGCUGUGGACUACAAUGAAUGAAUCACAUGUAAGAGAGAUCCAAGAUGAUGUUGGCAAGGUGACCAGGGUCCGGGGCUUAGUAUACCAUGCUGAGGAGUUUAGGUUUUAUCUGAAAUGCAACAGGAAGCUAUUGAAGGGUUUGAAUUGGGGCAGUGACAUGCUCUGAUUUGUAUUUUUACAAGAUCAUGCUGAUUGCUGUAUAGAGAGGUAUACAAAUUAUAAGGUUAAAAUGAUGACAGUGGGGAUGAAGAUGAUAAUGCUUAAAUGGGAAGACCUUGUGGUGGUCAUAGGAAGUGUUAGGAAUUACUUGCUUAUGUAUCUCUCAGGUGAAAGUACCGUUUGGGAACAUAAGGAAGGAACAGAUUUUUUUUUUUUUUUUUGAGGUGUUUGGAGGACAGCCAGUAGUUCAGACAUGUUUAGAGAUGUGUUUGGAUGAGAUAUCUGAGAGGAAAUAUCAAAUGGGAAGCUGGGUAUGUCGUCUGGAACUCAGCAAAGGUGUUUGGGCUUAGAGAUGGUACUUCUGAUUGAUUAGUGAGCCCUGGCUGUUAUUUAAAGCCCUGGGAGAGGAUGGAUGUAGGGAGAGUGUAGAAUGAGAAGGUGCUCAUUGAAGGACUCCUAUAGUGCAUUGGUCUCAGACAUUAGUGUUCAUUGUAAACAUUCAGAGGAUUUGGUAAAACAGAAGUGCUGAGCCUGGUCCCCAACUUUUGAUUAUGUCUGAGUGAGGCCCACUCUUUCAGUGAUACAGAUGCUGCCGGUUCAGGAACCACGUCUUGAGUACCGAGUACCACUGAUUUCGAGCGGGCGAAGAAGACUAAGAAGAAGGUGCUAGAGAGGUGGAUUCUCCACAGUUUUCCUCGUGCGUACUCACGGUGGAAUCCGAUGUGCAUUGAAGCGAAUGUAUGUCAAUAACAUGCCAGACCUCAAUGUUUGUAAAAGGGAAAUUACAAUUAUGAAAGAGCUAUCUGGUCACAAAAAUAUUGUGGGCUAUUUGGACUGUGCUGUUAAUUCAAUUAGUGAUAAUGUAUGGGAAGUCCUUAUCUUAAUGGAAUAUUGUCGAGCUGGACAGGUAGUGAAUCAAAUGAAUAAGAAGCUACAGACGGGUUUUACAGAACCAGAAGUGUUACAGAUAUUCUGUGAUACCUGUGAAGCUGUUGCAAGGUUGCAUCAGUGUAAGACUCCAAUAAUUCACCGGGAUCUGAAGGUAGAAAAUAUUUUGUUGAAUGAUGGUGGGAACUAUGUACUUUGUGACUUUGGCAGUGCCACUAAUAAAUUUCUUAAUCCUCAAAAAGAUGGAGUUAAUGUAGUAGAAGAAGAAAUUAAAAAGUAUACAACUCUGUCAUACAGAGCCCCUGAAAUGAUCAACCUUUAUGGAGGGAAACCCAUCACCACCAAGGCUGAUAUCUGGGCACUGGGAUGUCUACUCUAUAAACUUUGUUUCUUCACUCUUCCUUUUGGUGAGAGUCAGGUUGCUAUCUGUGAUGGCAACUUCACCAUCCCAGACAAUUCUCGUUACUCCCGUAACAUACAUUGCUUAAUAAGGUUCAUGCUUGAACCAGAUCCGGAACAUAGACCUGAUAUAUUUCAAGUGUCAUAUUUUGCAUUUAAAUUUGCCAAAAAGGAUUGUCCAGUCUCCAACAUCAAUAAUUCUUCUAUUCCUUCAGCUCUUCCUGAACCGAUGACUGCUAGUGAAGCAGCUGCUAGGAAAAGCCAAAUAAAAGCCAGAAUAACAGAUACCAUUGGACCAACAGAAACCUCAAUUGCACCAAGACAAAGACCAAAGGCCAACUCUGCUACUACUGCCACUCCCAGUGUGCUGACCAUUCAAAGUUCAGCAACACCUGUUAAAGUCCUUGCUCCUGGUGAAUUCGGUAACCAUAGACCAAAAGGGGCACUAAGACCUGGAAAUGGCCCUGAAAUUUUAUUGGGUCAGGGACCUCCUCAGCAGCCGCCACAGCAGCAUAGAGUACUCCAGCAACUACAGCAGGGAGAUUGGAGAUUACAGCAACUCCAUUUACAGCAUCGUCAUCCUCACCAGCAGCAGCAGCAGCAGCAGCAGCAACAGCAACAGCAGCAGCAGCAACAGCAACAGCAGCAGCAGCAGCAGCAGCAGCAGCACCACCACCACCACCACCACCACCUACUUCAAGAUGCUUAUAUGCAGCAGUAUCAACAUGCAACACAGCAGCAACAGAUGCUUCAACAACAAUUUUUAAUGCAUUCGGUAUAUCAACCACAACCUUCUGCAUCACAGUAUCCUACAAUGAUGCCGCAGUAUCAGCAGGCUUUCUUUCAACAGCAGAUGCUAGCUCAACAUCAGCCGUCUCAACAACAGGCAUCACCUGAAUAUCUUACCUCCCCUCAAGAGUUCUCACCAGCCUUAGUUUCCUACACUUCAUCACUUCCAGCUCAGGUUGGAACCAUAAUGGACUCCUCCUAUAGUGCCAAUAGGUCAGUUGCUGAUAAAGAGGCCAUUGCAAAUUUCACAAAUCAGAAGAACAUCAGCAAUCCACCUGAUAUGUCAGGGUGGAAUCCUUUUGGAGAGGAUAAUUUCUCUAAGUUAACAGAAGAGGAACUAUUGGACAGAGAAUUUGACCUUCUAAGAUCAAAUAGGCUCGAGGAGAGAGCAUCCUCAGAUAAGAAUGUAGACUCACUUUCUGCUCCACAUAACCAUCCUCCAGAAGAUCCUUUUGGUUCUGUUCCUUUCAUUUCUCAUUCAGGUUCUCCUGAAAAGAAAGCUGAACAUUCAUCUAUAAAUCAAGAAAAUGGCACUGCAAACCCUAUCAAGAACGGUAAAACAAGUCCAGCAUCUAAAGAUCAGCGGACUGGAAAGAAAACCUCAGUACAGGGUCAAGUGCAAAAGGGGAAUGAUGAAUCUGAAAGUGAUUUUGAAUCAGAUCCCCCUUCUCCUAAGAGCAGUGAAGAGGAAGAGCAAGAUGAUGAAGAAGUUCUUCAGGGGGAACAAGGAGAUUUUAAUGAUGAUGAUACUGAACCAGAAAAUCUGGGUCAUAGGCCUCUCCUCAUGGAUUCUGAAGAUGAGGAAGAAGAGGAGAAACAUAGCUCUGAUUCUGAUUAUGAGCAGGCUAAAGCAAAGUACAGUGACAUGAGCUCUGUCUACAGAGACAGAUCUGGCAGUGGACCAACCCAAGAUCUUAAUACAAUACUCCUCACCUCAGCCCAAUUAUCCUCUGAUGUUGCAGUGGAGACUCCCAAACAGGAGUUUGAUGUAUUUGGCGCUGUCCCCUUCUUUGCAGUGCGUGCUCAACAGCCCCAGCAAGAAAAGAAUGAAAAGAACCUCCCUCAACACAGGUUUCCUGCUGCAGGACUGGAGCAGGAGGAAUUUGAUGUAUUCACAAAGGCGCCUUUUAGCAAGAAGGUGAAUGUACAAGAAUGCCAUGCAGUGGGGCCUGAGGCACAUACUAUCCCUGGUUAUCCCAAAAGUGUAGAUGUAUUUGGCUCCACUCCAUUUCAGCCCUUCCUCACAUCAACAAGUAAAAGUGAAAGCAAUGAGGACCUUUUUGGGCUUGUGCCCUUUGAUGAAAUAACGGGGAGCCAGCAGCAAAAAGUCAAACAGCGCAGCUUACAGAAACUGUCCUCUCGCCAAAGGCGCACAAAGCAGGAUAUGUCCAAAAGUAAUGGGAAGCGGCAUCAUGGCACGCCAACUAGCACAAAGAAGACUUUGAAGCCUACCUAUCGCACUCCAGAGAGGGCUCGCAGGCACAAAAAAGUGGGCCGCCGAGACUCUCAAAGUAGCAAUGAAUUUUUAACCAUCUCAGACUCCAAGGAGAACAUUAGUGUUGCACUGACUGAUGGGAAAGAUAGGGGGAAUGUCUUACAACCUGAGGAGAGCCUGUUGGACCCCUUCGGUGCCAAGCCCUUCCAUUCUCCAGACCUGUCAUGGCACCCUCCACAUCAGGGCCUGAGCGACAUCCGUGCUGAUCACAAUACUGUCCUGCCAGGGCGGCCAAGACAAAAUUCACUACAUGGGUCAUUCCAUAGUGCAGAUGUAUUGAAAAUGGAUGAUUUUGGUGCCGUGCCCUUUACAGAACUUGUGGUGCAAAGCAUCACUCCACAUCAGUCCCAACAGUCCCAACCAGUCGAAUUAGACCCAUUUGGUGCUGCUCCAUUUCCUUCUAAACAGUAGAUACUUCUGAUGGAUUCUCGGCAUUAACUCCUGUUUCAAAAAAGUGUGAACAGUUUUAUGAAUUUGAAAGAAAAUUUGGUAGCUCUUUAUAGCAUUCAUUCUUAAAGAUCAGUCAGAAUAGGUGAUUUCUAAAUAAACCAAAUAGAAGAAUGAAGUAUCUCUACAGGGUAGUAACUUGAUUCCUCUUCAGGAGAAAAGGGAGCUAAAUUGCAAGCUCUAACUAAGGGUUUCUGCUACUGACAUCACAACACAGAAAUGCAAGUGUGGUACUUCCAGUGAAAGCACAUGGCACCUUUCUAGGUGUGUAGCCACUGAGAAGGGACAGUGAAACUGUUAUUUUUGAUAUCAGAAUGUCAUUUUUAUGUGCAUAUCCCUAAAAUUAGGGUUAUUUCUACAUACACUAGUUACACUUGUGAAUUUUUUUUAAGGUCUCUUUUAAUUUCCAGACAGUUAAAAACAAUCUAGUUAUCUUAAAGCAUUAGAAAGUUAUUAUCUGGAGAGUGCAGAGAUUUCAGUCCAUACACCUUUCUCCACAAAGCAGAGCCAGAAGUAACUGACUAUUGUGCCUAAAACUCUGUUUCAUUUUUAAAAACAAGUGCCAUUAAAAUGGAAUAUCUAAUGAUAAGCAUAUGAAAUAAUGUGUAAUUAGCUCAAUUUAACUAUUCCACAACUUACAUAUUCCAAAACAAUGUUAUACAUGAUAAAUAUAUAUAAUUUUUGUCAGUUAAAACAAAUUAAAAAAAUGGACUAUCGUCGCACAGAAGCCUAGAACAAAAAUAUGAAGAGAAAUAUCUGACAUUUGUAAAGAAAUUAUAAGAAGAAAAAAAGAUACAGAACAGAAAACAUUCACUACUUUAGAAACACUUUAUGCAUGGCUUCUUGCCCCAAACUUUUAUUGUGAUGGCCCUAAUAAAGCAGAUUAUUGGAAAAAUUGGAGGACAAGGGUUGUAUAAAAAUUUUAUUUUAUGAAGAAAAUAUGUAGCGGAAACUGAAUUUUCAAGACAUUUACAAUGUGAAAUCAUGUUGCAUUUAACAAUGUACUUUAUUAGCAACUUCACCAAAUAUUCCCCAAGUCAUAAGCAACAAUUAUUUUUAUUAGGUUUUGGGGGGUGGAGUAGUUUUAAUAAAGUGCACAGAAUGGUGACACCCACAAAGCCUUAUAUAAAGGCAGGAUUCAUGCAUCCUGCUGCAAGUACCUCUGCACUAAUAUACCAGAUCCUAAAAUGCAUAUAAGGUGGACUAGCAUCUUAAUUCUGCUAGUUGAUUGUGUCUUUACUGAAAAGAACCCAGCUACCAAUUUGCCUUUUUUUACACCACAAAUCCUAAUUAGAAACUUGAGGUUUUAUAGAAAUCAUUUAAUGAUAGAGAUUACAUAUGUGAAUUAAUGUGAAUAUAGUAUCUGUGCUUCCUGUGUCUAUGACUAUUUUAAGAUAUAAUUGUGCUGCGCUAUCAGAUUAACAUUUGGAAGUUUCUAGAACAGUUAAUGCUAUUUACAGAAAGGAGUAGAAACUCAUCAACUGGCACUCUCUUUGAUUUUUAUAUUUUAAAUUAACUCUCUUCGAUCUCAAAGUAUAUUUUACGAGUAAUUUUAUUAGGAAUCUCUUAUAGUGCCCCAAUGGGAUAAGCUAUUUGCCUAUUUUCACAGUUCUGAACUUGGAAAGAAGCAAAGUAUAUGUAACUAAACCACAUAUUUGUCUUUUUAUUGCUUUUUCCCUUCUUUUAUAUGCUAAAUCAAAUAUAGAUUUGUGGAUAGGGAAGCAAUAUGUGAAUCACAAUGUAGCAGAGGCAGACCAAGCAUUACAUUAUUAUUUAGAGCUGGACUGCACCAAUUACUUGUCCUCGUGCCAAAGGCAAAUAUGUUUGCACCUUUUUUUUUUUUUCUGAUUCUCAGGUUGAUUAAUACUGCUAAUGCAAAUGCUCAAGUAGAUGUUUAAAAACUUUACAAAAUAGAUUCAAGUGAUACUUUCUUUUAAAAGUGAAGAGUUGAUGAUUACACAUAGUAAAUUCAUGAACUACAGUAGGUUUGUAUCAAACAAUUUUUUUUAAUGAAAAUCUGUUGAGGUGUACACAAUAUGCUUCUUGAUUGUAUUAGUCCUUGGUCUCUGCUAGACCUCAUGAGUUUCAUCAUUUAGAAAAGGGGUAGAGGAUGAACUAAUGUCUCCUUCAGAUGUAAACAUGAAAUACCUAGAGUUUUACUUGCUUUUCAAUACACUGAAUAAUUUUAAAUGAUUCUGACACUGAUGUAGACCCUUUGACUUAUAAAUUCUGAGGAAACAACUGACAGCAUAAAAUAUUUACAUUCUUAUAACACAGCACAGUGACUUUCUUCUUUCAAGAUUGUAGCUCAGAGAAAAGAUACAGGAUUCAAUUGGGGGUUCAAUAGGAUAGAAAUGGAGAGAUUCCUUUGUGUUGUAGUAGAGGCAUUUUCCUAAGGAGUAUAGAUUUAUACUUUGCAUUUUCAUUCAUCAUCCCCCAGAAUCAUGGUCAAGGUGUAGGUCACUCCACACAGCUGAUGCUCAGGUUAUUCCCUUGUGAGAAUUAUGAGAAUAAAGCUCCCAAGAUAUGUGAAAGUGCUUAACACAGUACCUGGCACACAGCACUCAAUAAAAGUUUGGCUCUAUUAUGGGAUGGUUCAAUUCUGGUUUAAGGAAGGAAGAAAGGUUAUUAUAUAUGUACCACUAAGCAAAUAUAUAUAUAUAUAUAUAUUUGGGGUUUUUUUUCCCUAAUAUUAUUUGGGUGUCCCCUGUGCUUCUUUAGGAUGUAGUUAUAACUAAACCUGUUAUACUUGAACAUCACUAAGAGAAGUAAAUUAUUAUGAAGCUAGCAAAAAUCUUGAGGCCAAAGUUGUUUCUUAACAGCUUUAAUAAUGCUUGUUGAUUUUGAAUAAUCCUUUAAAAAGUGGACCAUUUGCUUAUUUUAAUAUCACGUCAGUAAAAUGUUAGUAUUAAAAAGAUCAGCUUUUUAUGGCAUUGAAGAAUGUAUCUGCUAAGACACAAAAAUUGCAUGGUAAGUAUAAUAGGUGGAGGAGGAAAGGUUGUAGGCCGGAUGAAAAUUUAACUGACUAGAACAUUUAUUCAGGAGUGUAAUUAUUUUCCCUUACCCCAAUCCCUGUGUACGUGUUGGGUAUAGUUACGACAUUAUCCGGAUUUGCAAAUAGACACAACUUUCAGUCUUACCCUGUUUAUUGUUUAAGAGUGAUAGACUGUUGUCCUCUUGCUGGUGGAAAAUCUAAGGUGGAGCCCACUCUUCUAUGCUGAAGUUCACCAGGCAGAGCAGUUUUCUUACAAGUCAGCUACUCUGCUUGGUUUAUUUUAGGUUUUGGUACUUCACGUAAGCACUGUUAGAAGGUACAAGUGUAUUAAUAUCACUAGUUUUGAGGCGCUUGGGUACAUUUGUUUUUAAUAUAUUUAGAAUGUGCAGUAAACUUUUUUCUCAUUUUUUUUUCUUUUUAGCAAACUUGUUAUUUUAGGUCCAAUUAUUGAGUUGACAGUCUACUGUGAGAAUGAGAUGACAUAUCUACUGUGAGAAUACCAUAAAUGAUGAAUAGUUUAUUUGAGAACUUUUAUACUCAGUGGUGUUUUAUAUAUUAAGAUAAAAAUAUGUACACACAUGCAUGUCACAUCUCUCUACUGUGGAGUUAAUGUGAAUUUUUAAAAAAUGGAAUUGCAACCACAAUCAUAUCUAAGAGAACAUUCACUCCUAGUGAGGGUUUACAAAAGCUACUAAGAGAAUAAGGUAGAUGAUAAUGCAAAGGGUCAUGAUUUGGGGUUAUUUUUGUUUUAUUUUAAAAUUUAUACUGCUACUUUUGAAAGAAUUGUUUUUAUGACUAUGCUCUUUUUGUGAUUGAAAAGUCAUCUAAUAGAAGCUGUAUAGAAGCUACUUUUUAAUUGCUGGCAAACAGCUUUAAGUGCACUUUCUUUGAUUACACUUCCAUUUUUUGUUAAACUUGAAUUUUCUGAAGCCUUUUAUGUACCACUAAGCAAAUAACUUUAACCUUUAAAUAAAGCAAAUUUACAUCUUUAUUGUAUUUCUACUUGUUACAAAACAUACUUGCUAAAGUAACUUCAGUCCUCAAAUAUAGCUGGGAAACAAUUAUGAGAUAGACUCAGUCUCCCCCUCCCACCCCUUUUCCCCUGCCAUAUCUAAUUAAGCACUAACUGAUUUUAUUACUUUAUUGCCUUUACACUGCUUAUUCUUUUUGACUGAAUUCUGUCCCUGAUUCACUGUUUUGUUUGAAAUUUAAAGUUAUUUUCUUACUGUAUUUAUCAUACCUGUUUUAAUCUGUUUUCUUUAAAUGCAAUAAAUCCCAAAUGGAUUGCAUAUUCUUUAUAA